GUGGUUCACUCACUCAGCCAGGGGUGUGGACCUGGGAGUGCAUAAGUGAGGGAAAUGUGUAUGUCCACAUGCUGUGUGCUGGUGUCCGGGCAUAUGUGUGAAAUGGAGGCAAAGCGGACAUUUAGGUGGUUGGGGGGCUUAGGAGAAGUGGCUGAGGUGGGGCAAUUACAGAGGUGCCCCUGGGGCAGGGGCCAUGCCCCCAUGUGUUUGAGAAGGGAUGGUGACAGACACAUCCUCUGGGUUCCAUGUCCCAUGCCUUCCUUCCCUAAGGGGUGGAAACCUAGGAGAUGCAAAUGCUUUGCCGGGAGUCAGGCUUCCCUGAAUGAAUGAAUGAGAGGUGGGCAUGGAGGGAACCCAGCCCCUCCAUUCACCUUGCUGUUCCUCCUUCCACAGCUGGGCUAAGGCAGGAGCUGCCAGGCAGCCAGGUUGGGCUUGGCUUGGGGCUUCCUGUUAGGGUGGGCCUUCUGGAGGUCACAGGGCCUGAGCAAAGAACAAGUGAAGAAAGCGGUACCUGACCUGGCCAUUUCUAACCUAGCAACUUACUCUCAAAGUGGGCAGGACCCAGUGAUCUUUCUUUAGGAUUUCGGGGCUGUUGAUGGGAAUGUUGUUACCUGGUCUCCUUUCUGGGAGAGUAGGGAGGAGGCAAUGCUCCAGACCCACCCCAAGAAGCAGAGCAGGCCUGAGGCCUACCCAGCCUGAAAACAAGCGUCAGUGAGUGCCCGGAGGGAGGGGACCUGGAGUGCCCAGUUCCCCAGAUGCUGUUUCCUGGCAGGGCUGAGUGAGAGGCAGACUGGCAGUGAGAUGUUGGCACUGAGUGGCUCUCCAGGACGUGCCAGAAAGGCUAGGUGAGGCGGAAGAAGCCAUCCAACUGGGUGUCAUCCAGAGUCUGAGGAAAGUCUGUUUCUAGACUGGGCAUACCUGGGGCAGAUCCCCGGGUAGGUGCUCUCCCCUUCACUGCCCGCAGAGAAGGCCAGGGUUUGAAUGGGAGCAAGUCUCUUCAGAAAGGUGGGCUUAGCAGUGGAUGGGAAGUUUUUUAGCACCAAGAUCACAGACUUCCUGGGGGUUUUCCACCUCCUUGUCUACUGGAGGCUCCCAUUCUGUGGAAGUGGGAGGGGGUGGGACAGUUGGGACCCAGCAGGGAGGCAGCCUGGGGCCUCAGAGGAUAUAGCAGAGAGCAGAGAACACCAGAGGAUGAGGUUGAGGCAUAGGGCUUGGCCUCUAUGCCUUCCCCAGGAGUGAGCUCCUGGCUGAUGCUUCUCAGAAGCCCAGACACCUUCUCCACCCUGUCCCUGUGAGCAGGUAUUCCCGACACAUGGGGGGAGACUGAGCUAAACCCCAGGUGGGGUGAUUCCUCAGGGCGGGAUCUCCAUGUACCUGGGGGUAGAUUGCCCAAUUCAUCUCUCUCCAUUUGCCUGCUCCCUCCCCAGCCCAUUCCCCCCUCAGGGCUACCUGGCCUCCCUGUGCAGUUUCUGGGUCUUGGCCCCUCUGUAGUGUCUGAGGGUUCCCCUUCAGUGGCACCUCCAGAGGUCUCUGAGUUUAGGACUUUCUGUCCCAUCUCUCUAACUGGGUCUCUAUUAGAGGGCUCUCUUUGCUGGGUCCUCCUGGUGGCCUUUACUGUUCAAGAUCUUCUUUGUAGGGUCUUCCAGUGCGCACCCUGCUGUGGGGUCUGUGAAGGAGGAUCGCUCUUCCCUCUAUGGAAUAUCUCAUUAUGGGUCCCUCUCUAGGGUCCCUUAGUCCAGGAUCCUCUUUUGGAAAUGUGGUCUCUUUUGAGUCCCAUUUUCCCCCGCCAAGGUAAUCCUGUAUCCUACUGAUCUUGAUAAAUAGUACUUCUCCUGUGAAUUCCCAGGGCUGGGUCCUUGGGGUCUCCUCCUUAAUUGACUUACUGGAGGAGUUUGGAUGGGGGAAGGAGGAGGAACAGGAGCACACAAACUAGAGCAUAGGCUUGCUCCCGGGUCGCCCACUCCAAGGGCUCCACUCGCACUGAGGCCAGCUGGAGUUAGCCCCAUUGUCUUGCUCUGAUAACCUGGGUACGAGCCAUGAUUCAGGUCUGCCUGGAGCCUUCGCACCUUGUACUUUAUAGAGCAUCUCUCACCUGGAAGCACAAAGACCUGAGCAGGCAGAGGGUCACCAGACACAGGGGCUCUGCAGCAAGGAGGGGCUCCCUGCUCCCUGACUAAAAACAGGCAGAGAAGUAGACCCGAGACAGCCAGCUAGGGAGGCAGAUAAGAGACAAAGGAAAACAGUGGGAAGCCAGCGGGCGGGGGCACACCUGGUUUGCCCCAGGUGUCUCUUUCUCUGCCCUUCUCCUCACUGUGAGCUUUUCCCCACCAAGGUUGGGAAAGGGGGGCUGAGUCUCACAGACGGGUGCCAAUUGGAGCUCAGGAAUAGCAUUUGGGUUGGAAGGCCUGAUGAUGGGACUGAGAAGAAAUGAGAGAAGUCUCCUCUGGCGGAGAGUUGGAGCCUUGGCUAGCUCAGAAGUGGGGCCGGUGGGUCCUUUGAAGUCUCCCAGUGGAAGUGCCGCCAUCAGCAGAUAUCAAGAUGAGUGGGGAUGUAGCCGAUUCCACGGAUGCUCGCAGCACUCUCAGCCAGGUGGAGCCAGGAAAUGAUCGAAAUGGCCUAGAUUUCAACAGGCAGAUUAAAACCGAAGAUCUCAGUGACUCCCUGCAGCAGACCCUCUCCCAUCGGCCAUGCCACCUGAGUCAAGGACCUGCCAUGAUGUCCGGAAACCAAAUGUCUGGGCUAAAUGCCAGCCCAUGUCAGGACAUGGCUUCCCUCCAUCCGCUCCAGCAGCUUGUGCUGGUUCCCGGCCACUUACAGUCUGUAUCCCAGUUCCUGCUAUCUCAGACCCAGCCUGGGCAGCAAGGUCUGCAGCCAAAUCUCCUCCCCUUUCCACAGCAACAAAGCGGUCUCCUCCUCCCACAGACUGGGCCGGGACUGGCAUCCCAGGCAUUUGGGCACCCUGGGCUGCCAGGAUCCUCUUUAGAACCCCACCUGGAAGCAUCCCAGCAUCUCCCAGUGCCCAAGCAUCUACCCAGCUCUGGAGGGGCCGAUGAGCCCAGUGACCUCGAGGAGCUGGAGAAGUUUGCCAAGACCUUCAAGCAGAGGCGCAUUAAGCUGGGCUUCACACAGGGAGAUGUGGGGCUGGCGAUGGGAAAGCUGUAUGGCAACGACUUCAGCCAGACCACCAUCUCACGAUUUGAGGCCCUCAACCUGAGCUUCAAGAACAUGUGCAAGCUCAAGCCCCUGCUGGAGAAGUGGCUGAAUGAUGCAGAGUCCUCUCCGUCAGACCCCUCAGUGAGCACGCCCAGCUCCUACCCCAGCCUCAGUGAAGUAUUUGGUAGGAAGAGAAAGAAACGGACCAGCAUCGAGACCAACAUCCGCCUGACUCUGGAGAAGAGGUUUCAAGAUAACCCAAAACCCAGCUCGGAGGAGAUCUCCAUGAUUGCAGAGCAGUUGUCCAUGGAGAAGGAGGUGGUGAGGGUCUGGUUCUGCAACCGACGCCAAAAGGAGAAGCGAAUCAACUGCCCUGUGGCCACACCCAUCAAACCACCUGUCUACAACUCCCGGCUGGUAUCUCCCUCAGGGUCUCUGGGCCCCCUCUCUGUCCCUCCUGUCCACAGUACCAUGCCUGGAACAGUAACGUCAUCCUGUUCCCCUGGGAACAACAGCAGGCCUUCAUCUCCUGGCUCAGGACUCCACGCCAGCAGCCCCACUGCAUCUCAAAAUAACUCCAAAGCAGCAGUGAACUCCGCCUCCAGUUUUAACUCUUCAGGAUCUUGGUACCGAUGGAAUCAUUCCACCUACCUCCACUGAGACCAAAAAGUUUCUCCUACUCCAGCUGGCCCUGUAUUCCCCCUGGAAGGAAGGGAAUCAUGCCUUCUAUAUACAGACAGAUUGCCUUCAGAAGAGUGGAAGAAAAUCUCCACUAUCAAUGAACCCAGACUCUUGUCUUCUUCAAGAGCAAGGGCCUCCGGAGAUCCAAACUGUGAUUGAACCAAGUGCAGACUCCUAAUGCUCUUGAAAUACACAGCCCCUCCUAGGAGCUUACCAUUUUCACCUUCCUUGCCUAUGCCCUUGCCUUCUAGUUCCAAAUAUUUUAGCCAGCUUCACUGUGGCAAUAGUCUUUCAGAGAAAAGACUUCUUGCUGUUAUUCUCCAACUCAUCCGUGGGCUUCUGGGGACAGCCAUUUGGCUGGGGUGCCAAACACCAGAAGGGGAGAUAAUAGUUUUGACUCUGAACUUGGCCACAACCCCUGAACUGAUCCCAAAAUCUGUGAAAAGAUUUGAAUCUGAUAUCUCCACCAAAGCCUUGAUGUUUUCUCUGUACAGCUAAGUUUUCUGAUGGAAUCUUCAUCUCACCCCAUUUUCUUUUUAACCUCGCCCCCUUUUCUACAAUCAAAUCCAUUCAUUAUUGCGCCCUCCAGGUCCCCUCCUUUUUGCAGAAGGUGUAAAAGAGCUGCCCUUGGUGGGUGCCCUGGGCAUGUUGCAACGCCUGCUGGUGCCCUUCUGUCUGUCCACGUCUGCCUAGGGCUCAGGAGUGCUUGUUCUUUCCCUUCCUCCCUGUGUUUCUCUUUAUCCUGUCCCCUCUCCUUUCUCCUGGCAGCAGAAAAGGAAGAACACAAGAGCAAACACACAACAAUGAUGGUGGCAAAGUACCUGUAUAUAGCCCUUUCCCAUUUUUUGCAUUAUGUUCUUAACUCCUUAAUGUGGAAUUUUCCAGCAAAAUGUUUAACUCAGGUGUGAUUUUUGAAAAUGUCUCUGUAAUAUUUUAUCUUCUUUAAAAAAAAGGGGGGGAAAUACCAAAGUGUGAAAUACUGUGCUACCUUCCAGAGUUCCCACAUGGGCUGGGAUUUUUUUUUCUUUUUCUUUUUUUUUUUUUUUUUUGAGACAGUCUUGCUCCAGCCCAGGCUGGAGUGCAGUGGCAUGAUCUUGGCUCACUGCAUGCUCUGCCACUUGGGUUCAAGCGAUUCUCCUGCCUCAGCCUCUCAAGUAGCGGGAUUACAGGCGCCCACCACCAAAAAUUAGCCCAGCUAAUUUUUGUAUUUUUAGUAGAGAUGGGGUUUCACCAUGUUGGUCAGGCUGGUCUUGAACUCCUGACCUCCUGAUCCACCCACCUCAGCGUCCCGAAGUGCUGGGAUUACAGGUGUGAGCCACCGCGCCUGGCCUGGGCUGGGAAUCUUUGUUGACUUCUUUGGGAACAUUAUCUCUAGAGUCUGCUUUUUUGUGGGCCAGUUUGUAGAGAUGUAACAUGAAGCCAUUCCAGAAAUGGUAACUUAAAAAAAAAAAGACUACAUGUCUAGGAAACUGUUGAGAUUCAAAGGAAUCUCACUGUUCCUAAAUAAAUGUGUAUAGUGAUUAUGAAAAGUA